GAGCGCCCCGUCCCGCCGGCGGCCGCGAGACCAGAGCGAGCGAACGAACCGCGGCGGUCCGGAGAGCCCCGAGCGCAGCGCAGGACCUGGGUACGCCGCGAGGAACCGUGCAGCCCAGCGCGGCCGCCCGGCCCGGGUCCAGCAGCCAGGAGAGCGCAGCGCUUCGAAGCCGAGUGCGCGCCACCGCCCGCGCCCCGCGCUGGGGAAUGCGCCCUCGGCGCGCCGGCCAGGGGGCGCCCGCAGCCCACCCCAGGGGAGGCGGCCCCGAGCGCCCCUGAGCCUUCCCAUGGCCCGGGCUGGGGCCCGGGCCCUCGGCUGCUGACGCGCCCGAAGCCCGCGGAACCGGUUAAGCCGCGGCCGCGGCGCCGAUCCCGGCUGAGGCGCAGCGGCGAGAGGUCGCGGGCAGGGCCAUGGCCCCGGGGGGCCGCUAGCGCGGACCGGCCCAACGGGAGCCGCUCCGUGCCGCCGCCGCCGCCCGGGCGCCCAGGCCCCGCCGCUGCGGAAGAGGUGAGUGCAGCGGGAACCGGGAGGGAGCGGGCAGGCGGCCGGGCCACCCCGCGACCCCUCUGGGACCCGCGGCACUGCAACUCCGCAGAAGUGUCCGGGGAGCGGGUCUCGUCGAGCCGGGGGGCUGCCCGCGGACAUAGGGGCAACAAGGCUGGGGUGGGAUUCUUACCUGUCCUGGAGGCCCGGACCCCUUACCUACGGGGCGGCGUAUGGAUGUGUGGAUGAUGUGGCCUGCGGGGUCACCCAUGUGCAAAGCAACUUUUUCCUGCAAGGUUCUGGGUUUCUAGAGAGUGGAGCCUGCUUCCUGGGCCCUAGGCCCCUCCCACAAUGCUUGUCGCCGGUCUUCUUCUCUGGGCUUCCCUACUGACCGGGGCCUGGCCAUCCUUCCCCACCCAGGACCACCUCCCGGCCACGCCCCGGGUCCGGCUCUCAUUCAAAGAGCUGAAGGCCACAGGCACCGCCCACUUCUUCAACUUCCUGCUCAACACAACCGACUACCGAAUCUUGCUCAAGGACGAGGACCACGACCGCAUGUACGUGGGCAGCAAGGACUACGUGCUGUCCCUGGACCUGCACGACAUCAACCGCGAGCCCCUCAUUAUACACUGGGCAGCCUCCCCACAGCGCAUCGAGGAAUGCGUGCUCUCAGGCAAGGAUGUCAACGGCGAGUGUGGGAACUUCGUCAGGCUCAUCCAGCCCUGGAACCGAACACACCUGUAUGUGUGCGGGACAGGUGCCUACAACCCCAUGUGCACCUAUGUGAACCGCGGACGCCGCGCCCAGGCCACACCAUGGACCCAGACUCAGGCGGUCAGAGGCCGCGGCAGCAGAGCCACGGAUGGUGCCCUCCGCCCGAUGCCCACAGCCCCACGCCAGGAUUACAUCUUCUACCUGGAGCCUGAGCGACUCGAGUCAGGGAAGGGCAAGUGUCCGUACGAUCCCAAGCUGGACACAGCAUCGGCCCUCAUCAAUGAGGAGCUCUAUGCUGGUGUGUACAUCGAUUUUAUGGGCACUGAUGCAGCCAUCUUCCGCACACUUGGAAAGCAGACAGCCAUGCGCACGGAUCAGUACAACUCCCGGUGGCUGAACGACCCGUCGUUCAUCCAUGCUGAGCUCAUUCCUGACAGUGCGGAGCGCAAUGAUGAUAAGCUUUACUUCUUCUUCCGUGAGCGGUCGGCAGAGGCGCCGCAGAGCCCCGCGGUGUACGCCCGCAUCGGGCGCAUUUGCCUGAACGAUGACGGUGGUCACUGUUGCCUGGUCAACAAGUGGAGCACAUUCCUGAAGGCGCGGCUCGUCUGCUCUGUCCCGGGCGAGGAUGGCAUUGAGACUCACUUUGAUGAGCUCCAGGACGUGUUUGUCCAGCAGACCCAGGACGUGAGGAACCCUGUCAUUUACGCUGUCUUUACCUCCUCUGGCUCCGUGUUCCGAGGCUCUGCCGUGUGUGUCUACUCCAUGGCUGAUAUUCGCAUGGUCUUCAACGGGCCCUUUGCCCACAAAGAGGGGCCCAACUACCAGUGGAUGCCCUUCUCAGGGAAGAUGCCCUACCCACGGCCGGGCACGUGCCCUGGUGGAACCUUCACGCCAUCUAUGAAGUCCACCAAGGAUUAUCCUGAUGAGGUGAUCAACUUCAUGCGCAGCCACCCACUCAUGUACCAGGCCGUGUACCCUCUGCAGCGGCGGCCCCUGGUAGUCCGCACAGGUGCUCCCUACCGCCUUACCACUAUUGCCGUGGACCAGGUGGAUGCAGCCGACGGGCGCUAUGAGGUGCUUUUCCUGGGCACAGACCGCGGGACAGUGCAGAAGGUCAUUGUGCUGCCCAAGGAUGACCAGGAGUUGGAGGAGCUCAUGCUGGAGGAGGUGGAGGUCUUCAAGGAUCCAGCACCCGUCAAGACCAUGACCAUCUCUUCUAAGAGGCAACAACUCUACGUGGCGUCAGCCGUGGGUGUCACACACCUGAGCCUGCACCGCUGCCAGGCGUAUGGGGCUGCCUGUGCUGACUGCUGCCUUGCCCGGGACCCUUACUGUGCCUGGGAUGGCCAGGCCUGCUCCCGCUAUACAGCAUCCUCCAAGAGGCGGAGCCGCCGGCAGGACGUCCGGCACGGAAACCCCAUCAGGCAGUGCCGUGGGUUCAACUCCAAUGCCAACAAGAAUGCCGUGGAGUCUGUGCAGUAUGGCGUGGCCGGCAGCGCAGCCUUCCUUGAGUGCCAGCCCCGCUCGCCCCAAGCCACUGUUAAGUGGCUGUUCCAGCGAGAUCCUGGUGACCGGCGCCGAGAGAUUCGUGCAGAGGACCGCUUCCUGCGCACAGAGCAGGGCUUGUUGCUCCGUGCACUGCAGCUCAGCGAUCGUGGCCUCUACUCCUGCACAGCCACUGAGAACAACUUUAAGCACGUCGUCACACGAGUGCAGCUGCAUGUACUGGGCCGGGACGCCGUCCAUGCUGCCCUCUUCCCACCACUGUCCAUGAGCGCCCCGCCACCCCCAGGCGCAGGCCCCCCAACGCCUCCUUACCAGGAGUUAGCCCAGCUGCUGGCCCAGCCAGAAGUGGGCCUCAUCCACCAGUACUGCCAGGGUUACUGGCGCCAUGUGCCCCCCAGCCCCAGGGAGGCUCCAGGGGCACCCCGGUCUCCUGAGCCCCAGGACCAGAAAAAGCCCCGGAACCGCCGGCACCACCCUCCGGACACAUGAGGCCAGCUGCCUGUGCCUGCCAUGGGCCAGCCUAGCCCUUGUCCCUUUUAAUAUAAAAGAUAUAUAUAUAUAUAUAUAUAUAUAAAAUAUCUAUAUUCUAUACACACCCUGCCCCUGCAAAGACAGUAUUUAUUGGUGGGUUGAAUAUAGCCUGCCUCAGUGGCAGCAUCCUCCAAAACUUAGACCCAUGCUGGUCAGAGACGGCAGAAAACAGAGCCUGCCUAACCAGGCCCAGCCAGUUGGUGGGGCCAGGCCAGGACCACACAGUCCCCAGACUCAGCUGGAAGUCUACCUGCUGGACAGCCUCCGCCAAGAUCUACAGGACAAAGGGAGGGAGCAAGCCCUACUCGGAUGGGGCACGGACUGUCCACCUUUUCUGAUGUGUGUUGUCAGCCUGUGCUGUGGCAUAGACAUGGAUGCGAGGACCACUUUGGAGACUGGGGUGGCCUCAAGAGCACACAGAGAAGGGAAGAAGGGGCCAUCACAGGAUGCCAGCCCCUGCCUGGGUUGGGGGCACUCAGCCACGACCAGCCCCUUCCUGGGUAUUUAUUCUCUAUUUAUUGGGGAUAGGAGAAGAGGCAUCCUGCCUGGGUGGGACAGCCUCUUCAGCCCCUUCUCCCCUCCCCGCCUGGCCAGGGCAGGGCCACCCCACUCUACCUCCUUAGCUUUCCCUGUGCCACUUUGACUCAGAGGCUGGGAGCAUAGCAGAGGGGCCAGGCCCAGGCAGAGCUGACGGGAGGCCCCAGCUCUGAGGGGAGGGGGUCCGUGGUAGAGGCCUGGGGCCGGUAGAGGCUCCCCAGGGCUCCCUUAUGUCCACCACUUCAGGGGAUGGGUGUGGAUGUAAUUAGCUCUGGGGGGCAGUUGGGUAGAUGGGUGGGGGCUCCUGGUGGCCUUCUGCUGCCCAGGCCACAGCCGCCUUUGGGUUCCAUCUUGCUAAUAAACACUGGCUCUGGGACUAGA